AGCCCGCGGCCAGGCAGCCGGGAGGAGCGGCGCGCGCUCGGACCUCUCCCGCCCUGCUCGUUCGCUCUCCAGCUUGGGAUGGCCGGCUACCUGCGGGUCGUGCGCUCGCUCUGCAGAGCCUCAGGCUCGCGGCCGGCCUGGGCGCCGGCGGCCCUGACAGCCCCCACCUCGCAAGAGCAGCCGCGGCGCCACUAUGCCGACAAAAGGAUCAAGGUGGCGAAGCCCGUGGUGGAGAUGGAUGGUGAUGAGAUGACCCGUAUUAUCUGGCAGUUCAUCAAGGAGAAGCUCAUCCUGCCCCACGUGGACAUCCAGCUAAAGUAUUUUGACCUCGGGCUCCCAAACCGUGACCAGACUGAUGACCAGGUCACCAUUGACUCUGCACUGGCCACCCAGAAGUACAGUGUGGCUGUCAAGUGUGCCACCAUCACCCCUGAUGAGGCCCGUGUGGAAGAGUUCAAGCUGAAGAAGAUGUGGAAAAGUCCCAAUGGAACUAUCCGGAACAUCCUGGGGGGGACUGUCUUCCGGGAGCCCAUCAUCUGCAAAAACAUCCCACGCCUAGUCCCUGGCUGGACCAAGCCCAUCACCAUUGGCAGGCACGCCCAUGGCGACCAGUACAAGGCCACAGACUUUGUGGCAGACCGGGCCGGCACUUUCAAAAUGGUCUUCACCCCAAAAGAUGGCAGUGGUGUCAAGGAGUGGGAAGUGUACAACUUCCCCGCAGGCGGCGUGGGCAUGGGCAUGUACAACACCGACGAGUCCAUCUCAGGUUUUGCGCACAGCUGCUUCCAGUAUGCCAUCCAGAAGAAAUGGCCGCUGUACAUGAGCACCAAGAACACCAUACUGAAAGCCUACGAUGGGCGUUUCAAGGACAUCUUCCAGGAGAUCUUUGACAAGCACUAUAAGACCGACUUCGACAAGAAUAAGAUCUGGUAUGAGCACCGGCUCAUUGAUGACAUGGUGGCUCAGGUCCUCAAGUCUUCGGGUGGCUUUGUGUGGGCCUGCAAGAACUAUGACGGAGAUGUGCAGUCAGACAUCCUGGCCCAGGGCUUUGGCUCCCUUGGCCUGAUGACGUCCGUCCUGGUCUGCCCUGAUGGGAAGACGAUUGAGGCUGAGGCCGCUCAUGGGACCGUCACCCGCCACUAUCGGGAGCACCAGAAGGGCCGGCCCACCAGCACCAACCCCAUCGCCAGCAUCUUUGCCUGGACACGUGGCCUGGAGCACCGGGGGAAGCUGGAUGGGAACCAAGACCUCAUCAGGUUUGCCCAGAUGCUGGAGAAGGUGUGCGUGGAGACGGUGGAGAGUGGAGCCAUGACCAAGGACCUGGCGGGCUGCAUUCACGGCCUCAGCAAUGUGAAGCUGAACGAGCACUUCCUGAACACCACGGACUUCCUCGACACCAUCAAGAGCAACCUGGACAGAGCCCUGGGCAGGCAGUAGGGGGAGGCGCCACCCAUGGCUGCAGUGGAGGGGCCAGGGCUGAGCCGGCGGGUCCUCCUGAGCGCGGCAGAGGGUGAGCCUCACAGCCCCUCUCUGGAGGCCUUUCUAGGGGAUGUUUUUUUAUAAGCCAGAUGUUUUUAAAAGCAUAUGUGUGUUUCCCCUCAUGGUGACGUGAGGCAGGAGCAGUGCGUUUUACCUCAGCCAGUCAGUAUGUUUUGCAUACUGUAAUUUAUAUUGCCCUUGGAACACAUGGUGCCAUAUUUAGCUACUAAAAAGCUCUUCACAAAAUUGUCUGCUGUGUUUGUCCCUGAGGGGAGGAGGUAGUGGGACCCUGAGGCAGAGGCCCUGCUAGAGCUGGCAGGUUCCCCUGGGGCAGACCAGAGCACCUCAGGAAGGGGCUGCCACGGCAGGGAAGGGACCAGGCAGCCCUGGGAGCCCGCAUUCCACAGGGGCCCACUGCGGAGUUCUCGGACACUCAGGGCACAGGCCUGUGGGUUCCCUGGAAUUUUCUAGCAUGAUCCAGUUUCUGUGUCCAGUUCUCCAUUCUGAGAGUCAAUCAGUUCCUGAUAGGUUGUCAUUGAUUUUUUUCUUCGUUGGUUUUAACCUUCUAAACAUCUCCAGGCCACUUUCUUAGCCUUUUUCUAGGUACUAAAAAGAGGUCCUACCCACACCUGCCUCACACUUCUCCUUUCCAAGGCUGCCUGAGUUUGGAGGGGCUUGGGUGUGUGUGAACAAGGGCCCUGCAUUGUCUAGGCCUGCAGUUCCCAGGCUUGGGUUCACUUUCACCAUGCAUUGGCAAAACUAGAAAAGUAAGCUUGUGACAAAUUGUUCUCGGCCGGGCACAGUGGCGCACGCCUAUAAUCCCUGUACUUUGGGAGGCUGAGGUGGGUGGAUCACUUGAGGCCAGGAGUUCGAGACCAGCCUGGCCAACAUGGUGAAACCCCAUCUCUACUCAAAAUACAAAAAUUAGCCAGGCGUGGUGAUGCGCACCUGCAGUCCCAGCUACUCGGGAGGCUGAGGCAGGAAAAUGGCUUGAACCUGGGAGGCAGAGGUUGCAGUGAGCCGAGACUGCACCACUGCACUCCAGCCUGGGUGACAGAGCAAGACUCUGUCUCAAAAAAAAAAAAAAAAAAAAAAAAAAAAAAAUUGCUCUAUGCAAGUUUUUUAGCCCCAUGUAAAAAGGAAAAAUAAAAGUUGCUCUAAAGCUACAUAUAAUCAAAA